AGUUGUGGGCGCCUUUGCAACCGCCUGGGACGCCGCCGAGUGGUCUGUGCAGGUUCGCGGGUCGCUGGCGGGGGUCGUGAGGGAGUGCGCCGGGAGCGGAGAUAUGGGGUCUGUGGUGAGCCAUAACCGGAGUCUGUGGACUGAACGGCGGGAGUCUAUGGGCAGAAUGAUGAACCAUCUGGGAGUUCUAUGGAGGGAGAUGGUUCAGACCCAGAGCCUCCAGAUGCCGGGGAGGACAGCAAGUCCGAGAAUGGGGAGAAUGCGCCCAUCUACUGCAUCUGCCGCAAACCGGACAUCAACUGCUUCAUGAUCGGGUGUGACAACUGCAAUGAGUGGUUCCAUGGGGACUGCAUCCGGAUCACUGAGAAGAUGGCCAAGGCCAUCCGGGAGUGGUACUGUCGGGAGUGCAGAGAGAAAGACCCCAAGCUAGAGAUUCGCUAUCGGCACAAGAAGUCACGGGAGCGGGAUGGCAAUGAGCGGGACAGCAGUGAGCCCCGGGAUGAGGGUGGAGGGCGCAAGAGGCCUGUCCCUGAUCCAGACCUGCAGCGCCGGGCAGGGUCAGGGACAGGGGUUGGGGCCAUGCUUGCUCGGGGCUCUGCUUCGCCCCACAAAUCCUCUCCGCAGCCCUUGGUGGCCACACCCAGCCAGCAUCACCAGCAGCAGCAGCAGCAGAUCAAACGGUCAGCCCGCAUGUGUGGUGAGUGUGAGGCAUGUCGGCGCACUGAGGACUGUGGUCACUGUGAUUUCUGUCGGGACAUGAAGAAGUUCGGGGGCCCCAACAAGAUCCGGCAGAAGUGCCGGCUGCGCCAGUGCCAGCUGCGGGCCCGGGAAUCGUACAAGUACUUCCCUUCCUCGCUCUCACCAGUGACGCCCUCAGAGUCCCUGCCAAGGCCCCGCCGGCCACUGCCCACCCAACAGCAGCCACAGCCAUCACAGAAGUUAGGGCGCAUCCGUGAAGAUGAGGGGGCAGUGGCGUCAUCAACAGUCAAGGAGCCUCCUGAGGCUACAGCCACACCUGAGCCACUCUCAGAUGAGGACCUACCUCUGGAUCCUGACCUGUAUCAGGACUUCUGUGCAGGGGCCUUUGAUGACCAUGGCCUGCCCUGGAUGAGCGACACAGAAGAGUCCCCAUUCCUGGACCCCGCGCUGCGGAAGAGGGCAGUGAAAGUGAAGCAUGUGAAGCGUCGGGAGAAGAAGUCUGAGAAGAAGGUGAUGGAGAGGAAGGAGGAGCGAUACAAGCGGCAUCGGCAGAAGCAGAAGCACAAGGAUAAAUGGAAACACCCAGAGAGGGCUGAUGCCAAGGACCCUGCGUCACUGCCCCAGUGCCUGGGGCCCGGCUGUGUGCGCCCCGCCCAGCCCAGCUCCAAGUAUUGCUCAGAUGACUGUGGCAUGAAGCUGGCAGCCAACCGCAUCUACGAGAUCCUCCCCCAGCGCAUCCAGCAGUGGCAGCAGAGCCCUUGCAUUGCUGAAGAGCACGGCAAGAAGCUGCUCGAACGCAUUCGCCGAGAGCAGCAGAGUGCCCGCACUCGCCUUCAGGAAAUGGAACGCCGAUUCCAUGAGCUUGAGGCCAUCAUUCUACGUGCCAAGCAGCAGGCUGUGCGCGAGGAUGAGGAGAGCAACGAGGGUGACAGUGAUGACACAGACCUGCAGAUCUUCUGUGUUUCCUGUGGGCACCCCAUCAACCCACGUGUUGCCUUGCGCCACAUGGAGCGCUGCUACGCCAAGUAUGAGAGCCAGACGUCCUUUGGGUCCAUGUACCCCACACGCAUUGAAGGGGCCACACGACUCUUCUGUGAUGUGUAUAAUCCUCAGAGCAAAACAUACUGUAAGCGGCUCCAGGUGCUGUGCCCCGAGCACUCACGGGACCCCAAAGUGCCAGCUGACGAGGUAUGCGGGUGCCCCCUUGUACGUGAUGUCUUUGAGCUCACGGGUGACUUCUGCCGCCUGCCCAAGCGCCAGUGCAAUCGCCAUUACUGCUGGGAGAAGCUGCGGCGUGCGGAAGUGGACUUGGAGCGCGUGCGUGUGUGGUACAAGCUGGACGAGCUGUUUGAGCAGGAGCGCAAUGUGCGCACAGCCAUGACAAACCGCGCGGGAUUGCUGGCCCUGAUGCUGCACCAGACGAUCCAGCACGAUCCCCUCACUACCGACCUGCGCUCCAGUGCCGACCGCUGAGCCUCCUGGCCCGGACCCCUUACACCCUGCAUUCCAGAUGGGGGAGCCGCCCGGUGCCCGUGUGUCCGUUCCUCCACUCAUCUGUUUCUCCGGUUCUCCCUGUGCCCAUCCACCGGUUGACCGCCCAUCUGCCUUUAUCAGAGGGACUGUCCCCGUCGACAUGUUCAGUGCCUGGUGGGGCUGCGGAGUCCACUCAUCCUUGCCUCCUCUCCCUGGGUUUUGUUAAUAAAAUUUUGAAGAAACCAA